GAGCAACGGCUCUGCGGCCAUGGCGAGCGGCGAGCAUUCCCCCGGCAGCGGCGCGGCCCGGCGGCCGCUGCACUCCGCGCAGGCUGUGGACGUGGCCUCGGCCUCCAACUUCCGGGCCUUUGAGCUGCUGCACUUGCACCUGGACCUGCGGGCUGAGUUCGGGCCUCCAGGGCCCGGCGCAGGGAGCCGGGGGCUGAGCGGCACCGCGGUCCUGGACCUGCGCUGCCUGGAGCCCGAGGGCGCCGCCGAGCUGCGGCUGGACUCGCACCCGUGCCUGGAGGUGACGGCGGCGGCGCUGCGGCGGGAGCGGCCCGGCUCGGAGGAGCCGCCUGCGGAGCCCGUGAGCUUCUACACGCAGCCCUUCUCGCACUAUGGCCAGGCCCUGUGCGUGUCCUUCCCGCAGCCCUGCCGCGCCGCCGAGCGCCUCCAGGUGCUGCUCACCUACCGCGUCGGGGAGGGACCCGGGGUUUGCUGGUUGGCUCCCGAGCAGACAGCAGGAAAGAAGAAGCCCUUCGUGUACACCCAGGGCCAGGCUGUCCUAAACCGGGCCUUCUUCCCUUGCUUCGACACGCCUGCUGUUAAAUACAAGUAUUCAGCUCUUAUUGAGGUCCCAGAUGGCUUCACAGCUGUGAUGAGUGCUAGCACCUGGGAGAAGAGAGGUCCAAAUAAGUUCUUCUUCCAGAUGUGUCAGCCCAUCCCCUCCUAUCUGAUAGCUUUGGCCAUCGGAGAUCUGGUUUCGGCUGAAGUUGGACCCAGGAGCCGGGUGUGGGCUGAGCCCUGCCUGAUUGAUGCUGCCAAGGAGGAGUACAACGGGGUGAUAGAAGAAUUUUUGGCAACAGGAGAGAAGCUUUUUGGACCUUAUGUUUGGGGAAGGUAUGACUUGCUCUUCAUGCCACCGUCCUUUCCAUUUGGAGGAAUGGAGAACCCUUGUCUGACCUUUGUCACCCCCUGCCUGCUAGCUGGGGACCGCUCCUUGGCAGAUGUCAUCAUCCAUGAGAUCUCCCACAGUUGGUUUGGGAACCUGGUCACCAACGCCAACUGGGGUGAAUUCUGGCUCAAUGAAGGUUUCACCAUGUACGCCCAGAGGAGGAUCUCCACCAUCCUCUUUGGCGCUGCGUACACCUGCUUGGAGGCUGCAACGGGGCGGGCUCUGCUGCGUCAGCACAUGGACAUCACUGGAGAGGAAAACCCACUCAACAAGCUCCGCGUGAAGAUUGAACCAGGCGUUGACCCGGACGACACCUAUAAUGAGACCCCCUACGAGAAAGGUUUCUGCUUUGUUUCAUACCUGGCCCACUUGGUGGGUGAUCAGGAUCAGUUUGACAGUUUUCUCAAGGCCUAUGUGCAUGAAUUCAAAUUCCGAAGCAUCUUAGCCGAUGACUUUCUGGACUUCUACUUGGAAUAUUUCCCUGAGCUUAAGAAAAAGAGAGUGGAUAUCAUUCCAGGUUUUGAGUUUGAUCGAUGGCUGAAUACCCCCGGCUGGCCCCCGUACCUCCCUGAUCUCUCCCCUGGGGACUCACUCAUGAAGCCUGCUGAAGAGCUAGCCCAACUGUGGGCAGCCGAGGAGCUGGACAUGAAGGCCAUUGAAGCCGUGGCCAUCUCUCCCUGGAAGACCUACCAGCUGGUCUACUUCCUGGAUAAGAUCCUCCAGAAAUCCCCUCUCCCUCCUGGGAAUGUGAAAAAACUUGGAGACACAUACCCAAGUAUCUCAAAUGCCCGGAAUGCAGAGCUCCGGCUGCGAUGGGGCCAAAUCGUCCUUAAGAACGACCACCAGGAAGAUUUCUGGAAAGUGAAGGAGUUCCUGCAUAACCAGGGGAAGCAGAAGUAUACACUUCCGCUGUACCACGCAAUGAUGGGUGGCAGUGAGGUGGCCCAGACCCUCGCCAAGGAGACUUUUGCAUCCACCGCCUCCCAGCUCCACAGCAAUGUUGUCAACUAUGUCCAGCAGAUCGUGGCACCCAAGGGCAGUUAGAGGCUCGUGUGCAUGGCCCCUGCCUCUUCAGGCUCUCCAGGCUUUCAGAAUAAUUGUUUGUUCCCAAAUUCCUGUUCCCUGAUCAACUUCCUGGAGUUUAUAUCCCCUCAGGAUAAUCUAUUCUCUAGCUUAGGUAUCUGUGACUCUUGGGCCUCUGCUCUGGUGGGAACUUACUUCUCUAUAGCCCACUGAGCCCCGAGACAGAGAACCUGCCCACAGCUCUCCCCGCUACAGGCUGCAGGCACUGCAGGGCAGCGGGUAUUCUCCUCCCCACCUAAGUCUCUGGGAAGAAGUGGAGAGGACUGAUGCUCUUCUUUUUUCUCUUUCUGUCCUUUUUCUUGCUGAUUUUAUGCAAAGGGCUGGCAUUCUGAUUGUUCUUUUUUCAGGUUUAAUCCUUAUUUUAAUAAAGUUUUCAAGCAAAAAUUAA